ACUUCUUUCAUAUUCUGUCACAGGCAAAAUAUUUUUAUUUUUCCCCCAUUUUAAAUGGAGAGCAGGAAACAGAACCCCUCAAACGAAACUUUAAACUUUGUGCUGACAAACAAAGAGCUUGAUCUUUUAGUAAAUAAAAGGCAGGUUGAUUUUUUUAAGUUAAAACUACACAGAUAAGGGAGAUUUCUUUGGCUUCCCACAUCAUAGGUCAAUUUUUUUAAAAGAUCGACCAACCCCCAUGUAUAGUCGGCCUAUGGGACCCCUGAUUAGUUUACUAUUUGCUGUCACUGAAUAUCUAAGUAAUAUUUAUAAUAAUGUAUUUUAAAAUUCCUCACCUUCUAUAGGACUACUUCCACUUCAAUAAUAACUGAUAUAUAUUGUUCACUUUAGUGUAGCACUGUUAGUUGCUAAGGCCAUGCAUUCUACAAAUUUUGUUUUUGUUUGUUAUAAAUCUUCCACAAAGAAAAGCAGGUAAUAAUUCUAAGAAAUGUUACUUUAUAUAAACUAAAAAUUUUAAUGAAGCUUUAUAAUGUCCAGUCCUUAUGCAAUUGUGCACAAUAUGUAACAAGUACUGAAUAUUUUCCCAUGGCUAAUACAGAUCAUAGUUCCCAAAAUAGCUAUUCUAUUUGUUGUCAUAGGUAAUAUAUGUUAUAAUAAAAAUAAAAUUAGCUAUAUAAAACAUAUAUCCUAAAGUUUAGUAUAUCUACUCAAGUUGUAAGUGACCUAAGUUAUAAUAAGGUUUUAAUUCAUUAAUCUAACUUGUAACAAACAUUAAUUUGUUUAUAUCUACAGACUUAAAACAUAUUCCCAAAUAAUCUUAGUAUCAUCAUAUAUCUGUAUGGAUGAAAUACAGUGUUCCAUAGCACAGGGCACAUCUCCUUAAAAAUUGAGGUUCUGAUGGUCAGACCGUUGGUAACAUGGUCCUGGGCAAGUCAUUUAAUUUUUAAGGGCCCUAAUAAUUUAAGCAUUUUGGAUGCUAAGUAAUAUUAUCUACGUAUCAUAUCUUACAUAUGAUCUUUAUAUAUCCUUAUAUGAGCAAUAUAUGCAAAUAUUUCUGCCAGAAUGUAUAUUUUUAAAAUUACUUGUAAAUAAUUUAUUAUAGACUCAUGCUGAAACAAAACCUAUAAAUAUCCUAGAUAACCAGUGCCACAUUAAUAAUUAUUUGAUUAAUAUCUUCACAGAAAGCUUCACUCUAUUUUUAGGAAAAGAAUAUUUCUCUGCUUUGAAGUAUUAUCAAACACCUUUCCAUGCAUGUAAACUAUAUAAUGCAGCAGUGUUCAAUGAACUUUUAAUCUAGAGUUGUAAAUACCCGUUGGCAUUGCAUUCUCUGAAGCCCAAAUCAGGAGAUUUGAUCCCAAAAUUGUAAUUGUAUGGGAGACAUCAAAAUUAUUUGAAAUUUCGGUUGUUCCGGAAAAUCCAGGAUGUAAUUUGCCAUAUGUAUGUUUCAUUUUGAUUAGCUUCCACAUGCUCCCAACUCGUACAAUAUAAAUCCAUGAGGCUGCAGGGGAGAGAAGGAGCUGACACAUAACCUUAGCUAGUUGAAAGCUGGAAUGAACUUCUUAGUAGAAGGAUCACAGACUAAGGACAUUAACCUCCAUGAAGCUGAAGAAACUUUAACCCGAAUAAAUAUCUUAGUUUUACUUAUUCCUUUUUGGCAAUUUAAAAAGAGCAAAUGGUUCUAACAAAAAUGCAGCUCUUCUGAAAACCUCUGUUGGUUUAGGAGAGGGGGAGACAGAGGGUUUAGACUAAGUCACCAGACCCAAACCUGAAUCUAAAGGGGUUUGUGCACUGCUUUAAGGAGGAAACGGUAUUUUACUAUUGCACGUGGCAAUAUUUAGUAUAAUAUUUCACUCUUCUCUUAGAUGGCUGCCAAGAGUAACAAUUAAAGUUUGCUUUUUCACAGAUGAAUUAUUCUGAAUGGGCUGGGCUCCCAGUGGGAUUGUUUUGUAAUUUUGUUGAUGGCGAGUCCCGUAUUUCAUCUAAACAGGAUCAUAAUAAGAUGACUUAAGAAAAAAAAAAAGUUAUUCUCUACUCUAAACGUUACCAUCCCCUCCCUAGAGUCCCACAGAUAAAUGUGAUUAAGGCAGAGGCUAGCAGGAGAAGCAACAUGCUUUGGGGAAGUGGAGAAUGCAGGGUACUAGGACUGCAGAAAGAUGCUAUGACUUUUUAUGAAAUAACAUCUGAAAGAACAAUAAAGAGCUAAUGGUUAGAAAAGGUUCCUACAACAAGAGCUCAACAAGGGCUUGUAUUUAAAUGAGGUCAGCCGGCUUUUGCAGGUCUUGCUUAGCAGGAAUCCAUAGUCACGUAUUUCUCCUUAGACUGGGAAAACGGAAGUUGCCUGCCUACAGAAGUGUGUGGUCCUGGGUGCCCUUCUUUGUCCCACCCAACUCAGCCCUAACACUGAGUAAAAUAUAUGUAUGAAAUGAAUCUGAAAACUCCUGUUCUUCCUUGGGCUUACUUUUGUUUUCCCAGUGUUGAGUAAUUUAUUAAUAACUUGUUGGAAAAGUAGUUUAAAAAAAAAUAGGAGAACAAUUUCACAAAUUGCUCAAUAGGUACCUGCCAGUAAUAGGGACAUCAGCGUCACCCAUCAGAAUUUCUUUCUCAUCACGUAAAGCAGAAGCCACUUAGAGUAGCAAACAACUCAGUUUUGGAGUUCAGACAUCACUAGACUUGAUAGUCUUUGUUAUCACUGAUAACUUCAGUAAAGCCAACACCCCAAUGAAUAGUCUCUACCAAAACCCUACCAAAUCCAUUUUAUCCAACCUCCUUACAUUUCUUCAGACAUACCCCCAUGUCCUACAUCCUAGGCAGACAGCAGGGCUGGAUGAUGUGUGAGCUAGACUUGUGUGCAGCCCUCCUGAAGGCAGACUUGAUCCAUUCUUACCCACAUGUGUUAUGGACUGGAACAGGGAAGGGUUUCUCGUCCUGAAGCAGCUACUGGCUUGGACAGAUUCUCAUUCAGGCCAGGAAGUUGGCCUUGAACAACUAAAGAAUGUGGCUUUCUGAUGACUCAUCUCUGUUUCUCUGAGAGUGGGGUUACCCUGGAGGUGCUCACUGAUGAGCUAGGGACAGAGAACUUUCUUCUCCUUUUUCUGUGCCCUCCUUAUAAAAGCACUCUGUAAAUGACCCUGUAAUGAGAUGACCUCACAGAGAGGGAAGACACAUGUAAACAUUCUUAUGUUAAUGGCACCUUAAUUUUCAACAAUUUUAAUCAAACUAAGAUUAUUCUAUCCUGCUGUUUCUUAAAUAAUAAUAACAAUCUCAUAGUAUAAUUAAAAUAUCUUUUCUGGUAGAUUAGUUUUUCACAAUAAACAUAAUCUGAUGAAUACAUACCUAUGGAAACUGACUAAACAUUGUUUGGCCUUGUUCAUCUUGUGAAUAAUCCUAGCUAAGUUUCAGACAACAGCUUUUGACUUUAAACCUCCUCCAGAGAUAGUUUUUUUAAUUAAAUGGUAUAAAUAUCAUGUACCUAUCAGAGAAUCUACUUUAGAUUGCCCAUGAGAAUAGGGAAUUAUUUGCCUUAGACCAGAUGAACAGAUGUGAUAUUCUGCUACCAGAGAACUGAAAUCCAAAUUCCAGUAUUUUGCUUCUGACCAAUAUUUGCAAUGCCAGAAGGUGACUUUGGCAUUCAGCUGUUUGGGGUUUUGUUAGUAUUAUUUCUUUCCUCCCCUUGAUCCCUUCCCUUUCUGCUUAGGAAAAGUCUUUUCUGUUUUGUUUUGUUUUCUAUUCUUUUUAAUUCUCCCUUGUGUUCCCUAAAGCAUAUGAAUUAGCCAUAAAAGUGAAGGCUUUUGCCAUUCCAGCUGGUUUUCCUUCCUGGAAUUUAAUGGAUGUUAUCUCUUCAUUUAUUUAUUUACCAAUAUUUCCUGAGCACUUUCAGCAUGCCAACCCAACACAUGUUGAAGUGAGCGCAGAAAGUGGGAGGGGAAGAAACGUCAGGGACACCAUGGCGUUGACUAAUCUGACCUGCCCUGGUGUAACUUACAUACAGAAACAGAAAUUUACACUCCAUCUCUUUUUUUCUUUAGUCAAGCCCCGACAAUCUGCCAGGUCAUGUUAGAUAAGUGUUGAUGAUCCUUCUCUCAUCAUCUAAAAUUCAGGUUAAUGUCGGCAGCAGAAGGCAUCUGCUAUAGAGAAUAUCUUCUGUGGUGUCUGAUGUGUAUUUUGACCAGCUCCAUUUGGGCAUAUAGUACAUGCAGAUCCAUAGAGCCAUGCGGAAGACUUUUAAUUCAGGCAUUUUUCAUAACCUACGGCUUGUAUCAUUUCAGGAAGAAGUUAGCUCUUUCUUGUGAUCUCCUCCCUUUUAGUGCUAUAAUCUGAGGAAACUGUAAAUCCACUGACCUCUCCCACCAGUGCCUGGGCUGUGCAGGCUGAUUCUUGGCCCGAGUCCUUAUCUUUGGUUUGGGUGUGAAGUUAUAAUUAUAAUUGAAUGCAUGCAACAUCAGUGAUCUAGUUUUCUUUUUUUCAAAGUGUUUAUAUUGGAUUAUAUGACUGUAUACAGUUAAACUCUCUUAAAUCUAGGAACAGGAAUAGACGUCAGAUAAUAAAUUAGGACCUUCUGUCAUCUUUACUAGGCGAAAGAAUGAAAAAAAUGUCAUUGAAAAUCAAAAAAUGACAACUAAGUGAGAGAGGUUACCACGCCUUCCAUUUCACUGCCCUCCCAGACUAUUGAGCCAUCUUUAUGGAUUUGGACUGAUGGACGCAGAAGCCAUGGUGAUGGAGGCAGAGAAGUGGACCACCGUUCCCCGGCAGCACGUGUGUGUGGAGAGCACAGACCGACAAAUCAAGACAAUCCGCCCUAACAGUGCAGUGCGCUCCAUCUACAAAGCUUCAGGCUGCUCGGAUAACCCCAACCGCCAUGUCAACUACCUGGAGCACGUCGUUGUGCGCAUCACCAUCACCCACCCCAGGAGAGGAGACCUGGCCAUCUACCUGACCUCGCCCUCUGGAACUAGGUCUCAGCUUUUGGCCAACAGGCUAUUUGAUCACUCCAUGGAAGGAUUCAAAAACUGGGAGUUCAUGACCAUUCAUUGCUGGGGAGAAAGAGCUGCUGGUGACUGGGUCCUUGAAGUUUAUGAUACUCCCUCUCAGCUAAGGAACUUUAAGACUCCAGGUAAAUUGAAAGAAUGGUCUUUGGUCCUCUACGGCACCUCCGUGCAGCCAUAUUCACCAACCAAUGAAUUUCCGAAAGUGGAACGGUUCCGCUAUAGCCGAGUUGAAGACCCCACAGACGACUAUGGCACAGAGGAUUAUGCAGGUCCCUGCGACCCUGAGUGCAGUGAGGUUGGCUGUGACGGGCCAGGACCAGACCACUGCAAUGACUGUUUGCACUACUACUACAAGCUGAAAAACAAUACCAGGAUCUGUGUCUCCAGCUGCCCCCCUGGCCACUACCACGCCGACAAGAAGCGCUGCAGGAAGUGUGCCCCCAACUGUGAGUCCUGCUUUGGGAGCCAUGGUGACCAAUGCAUGUCCUGCAAAUAUGGAUACUUUCUGAAUGAAGAAACCAACAGCUGUGUUACUCACUGCCCUGAUGGGUCAUAUCAGGAUACCAAGAAAAAUCUUUGCCGGAAAUGCAGUGAAAACUGCAAGACAUGUACUGAAUUCCAUAACUGUACAGAAUGUAGGGAUGGGUUAAGCCUGCAGGGAUCCCGGUGCUCUGUCUCCUGUGAAGAUGGACGGUAUUUCAACGGCCAGGACUGCCAGCCCUGCCACCGCUUCUGCGCCACUUGUGCUGGGGCAGGAGCUGAUGGGUGCAUUAACUGCACAGAGGGCUACUUCAUGGAGGAUGGGAGAUGCGUGCAGAGCUGUAGUAUCAGCUAUUACUUUGACCACUCUUCAGAGAAUGGAUACAAAUCCUGCAAAAAAUGUGAUAUCAGUUGUUUGACGUGCAAUGGCCCAGGAUUCAAGAACUGUACAAGCUGCCCUAGUGGGUAUCUCUUAGACUUAGGAAUGUGUCAAAUGGGAGCCAUUUGCAAGGAUGGAGAAUAUGUUGAUGAGCAUGGCCACUGCCAGACCUGUGAGGCCUCAUGUGCCAAGUGCCAGGGACCAACCCAGGAAGACUGCACUACCUGCCCCAUGACAAGGAUUUUUGAUGAUGGCCGCUGUGUUUCGAACUGCCCCUCAUGGAAAUUUGAAUUUGAGAACCAAUGCCAUCCAUGCCACCACACCUGCCAGAGAUGCCAAGGAAGUGGCCCUACCCACUGCACCUCCUGUGGAGCAGACAACUAUGGCCGAGAGCACUUCCUGUACCAGGGAGAGUGUGGAGAUAGCUGCCCAGAGGGCCACUAUGCCACUGAGGGGAACACCUGCCUGCCCUGCCCAGACAACUGUGAGCUUUGCCACAGCGUGCAUGUCUGCACAAGAUGCAUGAAGGGCUACUUCAUAGCGCCCACCAACCACACAUGCCAGAAGUUAGAGUGUGGACAAGGUGAAGUCCAAGACCCAGACUAUGAAGAAUGUGUCCCUUGUGAAGAAGGAUGUCUGGGAUGCAGCUUGGAUGAUCCAGGAACAUGUACAUCUUGCGCUAUGGGGUAUUACAGGUUUGAUCACCAUUGUUAUAAAACCUGUCCUGAGAAGACCUACAGUGAGGAAGUGGAAUGCAAGGCGUGUGAUAGUAACUGUGGCAGCUGUGACCAGAAUGGGUGUUACUGGUGUGAAGAGGGCUUCUUUCUCUUAGGUGGCAGUUGUGUGAGGAAAUGUGGUCCUGGAUUCUAUGGUGACCAAGAAAUGGGAGAAUGUGAGUCCUGCCACCGAGCAUGCGAAACCUGCACAGGCCCUGGUCAUGACGAGUGCAGCAGCUGCCAGGAAGGACUGCAGCUGCUGCGUGGGAUGUGCGUGCAUGCCACCAAGACCCAGGAGGAGGGCAAAUUCUGGAAUGAAGCUGUGUCCACUGCAAACCUAUCUGUGGUGAAGAGCCUGCUGCAGGAGCGACGAAGGUGGAAAGUUCAAAUCAAAAGAGAUAUUUUGAGAAAACUCCAGCCUUGUCAUUCUUCUUGUAAAACCUGCAAUGGAUCUGCAACUCUGUGCACUUCAUGUCCCAAAGGUGCAUAUCUUCUGGCUCAGGCCUGUGUUUCCUCCUGUCCCCAAGGCACAUGGCCUUCCGUAAGGAGUGGGAGCUGCGAGAACUGUACGGAGGCCUGUGCCAUCUGCUCUGGAGCCGAUCUUUGCAAAAAAUGCCAGAUGCAGCCGGGCCACCCUCUCUUCCUCCAUGAAGGCAGGUGCUACUCCAAGUGCCCGGAGGGCUCUUAUGCAGAAGACGGCAUAUGUGAACGCUGUAGCUCUCCUUGCAGAACAUGUGAAGGAAACGCCACCAACUGCCAUUCUUGUGAAGGAGGCCACGUCCUGCACCACGGAGUGUGCCAGGAAAACUGCCCCGAGAGGCACGUGGCUGUGAAGGGGGUAUGCAAGCAUUGCCCAGAGAUGUGUCAGGACUGCAUCCAUGAGAAAACAUGCAAAGAGUGCACGCCUGAGUUCUUCCUGCACGAUGAUAUGUGCCACCAGUCCUGUCCCCGUGGCUUCUAUGCAGACUCGCGCCACUGUGUCCCCUGCCAUAAAGACUGUCUGGAGUGCAGUGGCCCCAAAGCCGACGACUGCGAGCUCUGUCUUGAGAGUUCCUGGGUCCUCUAUGAUGGACUGUGCUUGGAGGAGUGUCCAGCAGGAACCUAUUAUGAAAAGGAGACUAAGGAGUGCAGAGAUUGCCACAAGUCCUGCUUGACCUGCUCAUCAUCUGGGACCUGCACCACCUGUCAGAAAGGCCUGAUCAUGAACCCUCGUGGGAGCUGCAUGGCCAACGAGAAGUGCUCACCCUCCGAGUACUGGGAUGAGGAUGCUCCCGGGUGCAAGCCCUGCCAUGUUAAGUGCUUCCACUGCAUGGGGCCGGCGGAGGACCAGUGUCAAACAUGCCCCAUGAACAGCCUUCUUCUCAACACAACCUGUGUGAAGGACUGCCCAGAGGGCUAUUAUGCCGAUGAGGACAGCAACCGGUGUGCCCACUGCCACAGCUCUUGCAGGACAUGUGAAGGGAGACACAGCAGGCAGUGCCACUCCUGCCGACCGGGCUGGUUCCAGCUAGGAAAAGAGUGCCUGCUCCAGUGCAGGGAAGGAUAUUACGCAGACAACUCCACUGGCCGGUGUGAGAGGUGCAACAGGAGCUGCAAGGGGUGCCAGGGCCCACGGCCCACAGACUGCCUGUCUUGCGAUAGAUUUUUCUUUCUGCUCCGCUCCAAAGGAGAGUGUCAUCGCUCCUGCCCAGACCAUUACUAUGUAGAGCAAAGCACACAGACCUGUGAGAGAUGCCAUCCGACUUGUGAUCAAUGCAAAGGAAAAGGAGCGUUGAAUUGUUUAUCCUGUGUGUGGAGUUACCACCUCAUGGGAGGGAUCUGCACCUCGGACUGUCUUGUGGGGGAAUACAGAGUGGGAGAGGGAGAGAAGUUUAACUGUGAAAAAUGCCACGAGAGCUGCAUGGAAUGCAAGGGACCAGGGGCCAAGAACUGCACCUUGUGCCCUGCCAACCUGGUGCUGCACAUGGACGACAGCCACUGCCUCCACUGCUGCAACACCUCUGAUCCCCCCAGUGCCCAGGAGUGCUGUGACUGCCAGGACACCACGGACGAAUGCAUCCUUCGAACAAGCAAGGUUAGGCCUGCAACUGAGCAUUUCAAGACAGCUCUGUUCAUCACCUCCUCCAUGAUGCUGGUGCUUCUGCUCGGGGCAGCUGUGGUAGUGUGGAAGAAAUCUCGUGGCCGAGUCCAGCCAGCAGCAAAGGCCGGCUAUGAAAAACUGGCCGACCCCAACAAGUCUUACUCCUCCUAUAAGAGCAGCUAUAGAGAGAGCACCAGCUUUGAAGAGGAUCAGGUGAUUGAGUACAGGGAUCGGGACUAUGAUGAGGAUGAUGAUGAUGACAUCGUCUACAUGGGCCAGGAUGGCACAGUCUACCGGAAAUUUAAAUAUGGGCUGCUGGAUGACGAUGACAUAGAUGAGCUGGAAUAUGAUGACGAGAGUUACUCCUACUACCAGUAAACAGGCACUCCCCCACCAACACCACCAUUCCACUCUCAGGCAUGCCUGUGAGCAUCACUGUUUUUGGUUUUAUCCCCACACCAGGCUGAUGUGUGAGUUUUUCUAUUUGUCUUCUUUAACCAUGAGUCCAACCAGAAUAUGUAAGAAUGAUGAAAUACUUUGUUCUUCUUUUGAGUGGCUAAACUCAAUUAACAGUUCCUGUUCAACCGUAAUUGAAGAGCAAGGAUAAAAUUCAGAGGCAUUUUCCUCAAAAUAAUGUGUUAAGACACAAAAAUGAAGGAAGUGAAAACAAAUGAGAUUUGUACAAACUCUUCUAUGUGAUUUUAAAAAAAGGACAGCAGAUCUAUAGAAAUUCUGUUUCCGAGCUGCAUUGUGGAGGUGUCUGCUGCCUCCUGGUAUUCUAAUUUUUCUUUAUCUAAUUUUGGGGAUAAUGGAGGUACAAAGGAGUUGUUGGUUUGGUGGUGUUUUUCUUCCCUUUAGCUGUCUUUAGGCAGAAAUUUGUUUUGUAAGGGCCAAGAAAAGAGGGCUCUUAUCAAUUGACUCCAGGCCACCCCUGGUGAGCAGAAGAGACCACCUGGGCUGGGCUGCUCAGGACCUACUUGAGAUAAGGGAAGAAAAGAGAAGGUGCAUCAUAGCUGAGGAGCCAUGAGGUCACCCCAGGCCCUAGUUCCUCCGCAGGAAUCCAGAGUCACAACAAUUCUAAAGGCAGAGCAAGCCCAGCGAGAAAGAAAUAACUGAAUUUCCAGGAACUGCACUCUCAUGAUUUUCUGGGUACUUUUCGCCUGGGAGACAUCAGCUAAGACAUCGAAUAAUAAAAGAAAAAUGGCAGUGUUAACCUAACAUAAAAUGGAAUAAAAUGACAAACACUUCAUCCGCUCUAAAAAAUUCAGAGCUUUCCUUCAUCAACAACCCAUCACAAAACCGUGGACUCUCAAUAGAAAGAGUUGGAAUAGAGUCUAACAUGGAAAAAAAAAAAUCCCAAUAUGCUGCUCACAAGCUGUACUCUAGCUGCUGACCAGCCUUCCAGCACUGCUCAUCACUAUGAUUUUUGUUUCUAGACUUCCUAGGCUUCCUUUUUUCCAUUCUUCUGUCAAGUGUAUUCUUGGAUUCAUGCAACUGAGGACAGUUUUUGUCCAGAUUGUAACACAGAGAAGGGCUCUUGCUAUGCAAAAUGAUGUUGGCAGGGUCUUACAGAUUUCCUUGUCAAAAUAGACCUUACAGGCAGUACUAGAAAUGGAGCACCAGAAAGCAAAAAUGACAUUUUCAGAGAAUGAUGAUAAUUAUAAUCUAUUGCACACCUACUACCAGAUAACAAGCUAAGUAAUUCCCCCCCAAAAAUGCCCCACUUAUCCAUUUUGGUACUUACCAUACUCCCAUGAGGUUGGUAUUGCUAUUAUUCUGUUCUUGUAGGAAACCUGAGGCUUACAAGAGGUUAGGUAACUAGUCCAAGGUCAUGCAAAGCUCAACAAAAUUCAAGAAAAAAGAAUGAUCACCCUAAAGCGUGUGUUCUUAUAACUAUGCUACUGAAAUAAGGUGGGAAAAUAAGCAUCCUAAAUAUAAUUAAAGUCAUGCCUAUUGUUUUAGUCUAUAAUAUCAAUGUUAUCUUUACUAAAUUCAUGGAUUUUCUUUUUUUAACAUAAUGUAUCACUGACACAGAAAAUCUUUAUGAAGAAGUCUUCAGUUUACUAAAGGCUUGUGCUUCUUUAGAGGAAAGCUCUUAAAACAGGGUUGACAAACAGUCUCUGGAAAGAGCCAGCUAGUAAGUACAUUAGGCUUUCUUGGCCAGAAAGUCUCUGUCAUAACCACUCAGCUCUGCUAUUAUAGCAUGAAUGCAGCUGGUACAUAACGGAUGGGUGAGCUGUGCUUCAAUAAAACCUUAUUUAUGGACACUGACAUUUGAAAUUCAGGUAAUUUUCACAUAUUAUAAAAUUUUAUUCUUCUUUUGAUUUUUUUCAACCUUUUAAAAUUUAAAAAUGCAAAAGCUAUUCUCAGUUCACAGCAUUACAAGAACAGGUGGUGGGUCAGAUUUGGCCAACAGGCUGUACUUUGCUGACUUUAUCUUUAAAACAGUUUUCAGAGAUCAUACAUGUACAUGUAUGAUAUGCCUCCAAAAAUUUUGAUCAUUUAAAAUUAUCUCCUUGGCCAGGCGUGGUGGCUCAUACCUCUAAUCCUAGCACUUUGGGAGACUGAGGCAGGCAGAUCACCUGAAGUCAGGAGUUUGAUACCAGCUUAGCCAACAUGGUGAAACCCCAUUUCUACUAAAAAUACAAUAAAAAUCUGGGCAUGUUGGUGCACACCUGUAAUCCCAGCUACUCAGGAGGCUGAGGCAGGCAAAUCACUUGAGCCCGGGAGGCAGAGGUUGCAGUGAGCGGAGAUGGCACCAUUGCACUCCAGCCUGGGUGACAGAGCAAGACUCCAUCUCAAAAAAUAAGUAACUAACUAACUAACUAAAUAAAUAAAUAAAUAAAAUUAUCUCCUUGCCAGGACUGCUGGCUCAUGCCUGUAAUCCCAGCACUCUGGGAGGCUAAGGCAGGAGGAUUGCUGACCCACCACCUGUUCUUGAGCCCAGGAGUUCGACAUCAGCCUUGGACAACAUAGUGAGACUCCCGUGUCUACAAAAAAUUUAAAAAUUAGCCAGGCAUGGUGGCAAGUGUCUGUAGUCUCAGCUACUCAGGAGGCUAAGGUGGAAGGAUCACUUGAACCCGGGAGGUCGAGGCUGCAGUGAGCUGUGAUCUUGCUAUUGCACUUCAGCCUGAAUGACAGAGCUAAGACCCUGACUCAAAAUAAAUAAAUAACAUUAUCUCUUCAAAAUGUAUCUGAAGCCCUGAUAGUUCUACUUUCAAUUCUUAGAAACAUAUAAAAAUAUAUGCAUGAUAGCCAUCAUAUCAAUGGAAGACUUUCUCACCUCUGUGGUUGCAGUUAGCUUACAAAAACGAGCAAUUUUGCUUAUACUGUGUUGUUCAUCUUCCUUGUUAAUUCUAAAGCUCUGAUAGACUGAGUUUGACAUUUCUUUCUGUAAACUGGAAAUUGUUUUCUAUGAAAAAAAAACUCUAUGAUACACAGUUAAAGAUUGGUUGAGGUUGAGAUGAACUUCAAUACUAAGAAAAAUUGUGGUGUUCCUCUGUGUGGCCUGCAAUGAAAAGAAGGCUCAUGCUUGUGUAUUGAGGUUUGACAUCUUUCCUUCUUUGUUUUUAGUCAUGCAACGUCAUUCUUAGAUGGCUUUUGAAUACUAUGCUAAUGACUAUCUAAAUAGAUAAAUAUGUGAUUGGAAAACAAAGUCACCUUUUAGUUUUCUACUUGGAAAUAUUAAGAGAAUCCUUGUAGACUGGAAACACACCAAAAGGCUGGGUAAAGCAUGGGAGGUUCCAGUUAAUAGAAAGUAAUUUUAAAAUUGGAAAUAAAAUUAAAUCAAGACCAGAUAAUGCUAUGGAGACUUACUUAUUAAAUAACUUUCUGAGCAUUUUUAUGUGCUUAGCAUUACAUUUUCCAAGUAAGAGAUACACAACAAGAGUGCUAUUUUUUCUUCUUUUUAUCUUCCUACACUCAAAGACCAAGCUAGCUUUAUCAAUUCUGAAUUUUCUCUCCUAAAAAUCAGCUCAAUCUGUCUUUCUGCCUCAUCAGCACUGCCUCAAUCUAAGGGAGGAAACCACCCCUCAUAUUGUCUUAUGCCCAAUUUCUGCCUCCAAAGAAAGAAGAAGUAAAAACUAAAAGGCAAAAAUGAAAUCCACAGGCAGACAGCCCGGCGCUACGCCCUGGGCCUGGCAGUUAAAGAUCGACCUCUGACCUAACCGGUUAUGUUAUCUAUAGAUUCCAGACAUUGUAUGGAAGAGCAUUGUAAAAAUCCCUGUCCUGUGCUGUUUCGUUCUGAUUACUGGUGCAUGCAGUCCCCAGUCACGUACCCCCUGCUUGCUCAAUCGAUCAUGACCCUCUCACGUGGACCCCCUUAGAGUUGUGAGCCCUUAAAAGGGACAGGAAUUGCUCACUCGGGGAGCUCGGCUCUUGAGACAGGAGUCUUGCCGAUGCUCCUGGCCGAAUAAACUGCUCCUUCUUUAA